ACUCAGAAGCGGGAGUCUCCGAGAGAAGAAAAGCAGGUGGAAGGAGAGGAAGCGGAUGCCGUGGGGUUUACAGCAGGAAAAUCCGUGGAGACAGCAGAUCCGAGAAGCGGCGAUGUUUGCGUAGAACCCUGUACGUGCUUCCUUCGGCCUGUCGCUCUUCCCUUCUCUCUGACCAGCACCAUGCUUCUCCUGGUGACAAGCCUUCUGCUCUGUGAGUUACCACACCCAGCAUUCCUCCUGAUCCCAGAGAAAUCGGAUCUGCGAACAGUGGCACCAGCCUCUAGUCUCAAUGUGAGGUUUGACUCCAGGACGAUGAAUUUAAGCUGGGACUGCCAAGAAAACACAACCUUCAGCAAGUGUUUCUUAACUGACAAGAAGAACAGAGUCGUGGAACCCAGGCUCAGUAACAACGAAUGUUCGUGCACAUUUCGUGAAAUUUGUCUGCAUGAAGGAGUCACAUUUGAGGUUCACGUGAAUACUAGUCAAAGAGGAUUUCAACAGAAACUGCUUUAUCCAAAUUCAGGAAGGGAGGGUACCGCUGCUCAGAAUUUCUCCUGUUUCAUCUACAAUGCGGAUUUAAUGAACUGUACCUGGGCGAGGGGUCCGACGGCCCCCCGUGACGUCCAGUAUUUUUUGUACAUACGAAACUCAAAGAGAAGGAGGGAGAUCCGGUGUCCUUAUUACAUACAAGACUCAGGAACCCAUGUGGGAUGUCACCUGGAUAACCUGUCAGGAUUAACGUCUCGCAAUUACUUUCUGGUUAACGGAACCAGCCGAGAAAUUGGCAUCCAAUUCUUUGAUUCACUUUUGGACACAAAGAAAAUAGAACGAUUCAACCCUCCCAGCAAUGUCACCGUACGUUGCAACACGACGCACUGCCUCGUACGGUGGAAACAGCCCAGGACCUAUCAGAAGCUGUCGUACCUGGACUUUCAGUACCAGCUGGACGUCCACAGAAAGAAUACCCAGCCUGGCACGGAAAACCUACUGAUUAAUGUUUCUGGUGAUUUGGAAAAUAGAUACAACUUUCCAAGCUCUGAGCCCAGAGCAAAACACAGUGUGAAGAUCAGAGCUGCAGACGUCCGCAUCUUGAAUUGGAGCUCCUGGAGUGAAGCCAUUGAAUUUGGUUCUGACGACGGGAACCUCGGCUCUGUGUACAUUUAUGUGCUCCUAAUCGUGGGAACCCUUGUCUGUGGCAUCGUCCUCGGCUUCCUCUUUAAAAGGUUCCUUAGGAUACAGCGGCUGUUCCCGCCAGUUCCACAGAUCAAAGACAAACUGAAUGAUAACCAUGAGGUGGAAGACGAGGUAGCUCUCCAGAGAAAGACCCUGUAAGUAUCUUUUUCUUUCUCAAUGACAUCCUGUGAUUGGGCCAUGAGUCACCUCCAAGUUCAGUGCUCAUUUCAUGGAACUGUUUAGCUGUGGGGCCCCACUGAACCCUUUGUGGUCACGCGGCAGCUCUCGGAGGAGCCACGGUUCUCCUGAACGCCCCUGGCUCAGCUACUCAACAAUCACACAAUGGACAGAGCGACGUCCUUCCUCCAAAGCUGCCCACUGAGAGAUUUUCAGGUCAAAAAUUGUAGUGCGUUGAACAGUGACCCUUAACAUUUAUGUCCACGUUAACCUCAGAAUGGGACAUUAUUUCAAAAUAAGGUCUUUGCAGAUGUGAUGAAGGAAAGAAUCUGAAGAUUGGCCGGGCGCGGUGGCUCACGCCUGUAAUCCCAGCACUUUGGGAGGCCAAGACAGGCAGAUCACGAGGUCAGGAGAUCGAGACCAUCCUGGCUGACACGGUGAAACCUCAUCUCUACUAAAAAUACAAAAAAUUAGCCGGGCGUGGUGGCGGGCGCCUGUGGUCCCAGCUACUCGGGAGGCUGAGGCAGGAGAAUGGCGUGAACCCGGGAGGUGGAGGUUGCAGUGAGCCGAGAUCGCGCCACCGCACUCCAGCCUGAGCGACAGAGCGAGAUUCCGUCUC